AAAGCUCCACCCUCCAGGAAGCCAGCUCUCACUUUUCACACAUUGGCCAAGUGUCCUGGACUCCUAAGGUGCAGGCCAUUUCUUUUUCUGUCUUGUAAUUUCCUGUUUCCUCCUGCCUCUCCUACUGACCAUAUCUUGAGAGCAGGACUGUCUUUUUCUCUGAUGUACUUCGAGAGCCUGCACAAGAGUGUGUUGACUAAAGCAACCAAUGGCGGUCCCAGCUAACGUGACCGCUUCCUAUUUUGAACUUCAAAGCUCUCCAUCCAGGAUGCCUCUUAAGGGCCAAAGUGCCCCAGCUGGAAUUGGAACCCUCCCAGGCAUAUCCAGUGUGUGUCCCACUGCCCGGUCGCCUGUGCAUGGGUCUAUCAUUGCCUGGAAUUGGUGGGCAGAGGAAUGAUGGUCAUGGAUAAGGGACCAUCCCUCCAAAGCGCAUCACCUCUUCUUUCAGUGGUCACAUUCAGGCCCUAGCUCCUCACUCAGGUAGGUGGUUUCUGGCCUGUUGUCCCAGGCAGAAAGGCACUGUGAUUAUGACAGGGCUGAGCUCCCAGUUCCUGGGCUAGAACUCCGCCCAUUCCCCACCCACACUGCCUAUACCUGGCUGGCUCUGGUUCCUGGCCCCAAGGUCUCCCCACCUGCUCCUUGGUAACAUCACCCCUUGACACACCCUGCCCUUGAUGAGGCCUCCCUGGCUCCUUGUCAGAACUCCUUGUUUAGGGGUCAGAGCUGUCCUCAACCUCCCACAAACAGGAAGGGCCCCACACCAAUGCUGAUUUCCCAGAGGACAACAGGCCAGUGAAACAUGACAGAGCGAGGGGCCACAGCCUCCGCAGGCCUCCCUUGAUUCUUCAAGCAUUAACAGAGCCCCAGCCUCUGAUCUAAGUGCUGCCCAUGAGCAGCAGGGUGCCUUGCAUCAGGCCUCCAAGGAGCAGCAAGUUCUCUGCUGGCCUCUGACAUAAGGGUGGAAGGAAGGAAACUAAUAUUUAUGAGACACCUACCUGGUAGCCAAACUCUGAGCCUCACAUUCUCCUCAUCUCUUUAUCUGGUCAGCUGUAGGUAUUAUUAUAAUUCCCAUUUUAGGGAGGGGGACCACCCCAUAGCACAGCUCCGGAAGGUGCCACUCUCAACUCCCGCUGUGCAAUAUACAGCCUGCUCUGGCAUCCAGAGGGGCCCUGAGAGAGGGUCCCAGAGCCAGCAUGUGGUUCCAGAGCGACCAACUCAGAAGCACCUCCAGCCAACUUCACGAGCUGGGACCCAGACACAUGUUUUUAAUGCAAGUCAUGCGGAGGCAGUGGCCUGUCGCAGCAUGCUCUUGAGCGCCUGGGUGGAGACAUGCAGAAGGGGUGGGAAGAGCAGGACUCUCGGUGCCCGUGGGUCUGGCAAGAACCCAUUAGCUCUAGUGCAACUCUUGCUAUCAUUCCUGCUUUCCCCAUCUGCUGUCUGUCACUCUGGUGGCUCUUGGUGUGUCUGUCCUCUUCACCAUUGACCCAGAGCCUUGCACGGGCUUUCACACAGUUGGCACACAAUGUAUGUUGUCAUGUCUGGCCCGAUUAACUGAUGCCUGUGUAUGGGCAUCAUCCAGAAUGUUUCUGGAUGGCCCUGGGCAUCUGGGGAGUGGACCACAAAGGCAGAUCCCAGGGGCCACUUAGUGCCAGCCCACAGUCCUCACCUUCACAGGUUGGUAUCCAGAUACUAUUUUUUUUUUUUUUCAAUUGACCUUAAGGAAACAGGAGAUUUGGUCAGUUUCCUCAAAGUUGCCUGCAGAGCAUGGGAGGCAGAGGUCAGGGAAGUGCAGGAAGGAUCCAUGACACAAGGCUAAACUGGGAACUGGAAGAAACUGCUCCCUGGCGGCUUUGUUCCUGACGAAGAUGGUUAUUUUUCCAGGAAUGCUGAGGAAAUCCACAGCAGCUUUAGUGUUCCCGCCUUGGAGAAAAUGUCUGGGGCAGGCAAGGGAGGUGGGGUGGAGCUAAUGGAAGUGAGGAUGGGAAGGUGGUGGAGAGGGCAGUUAAUCCCAGGAAGAGUCAGGGGUUAGAGAGUAAACUAAGACUAGAUCCAUUCCUUGGAGCCAGCCACUGCCCCUCCCCCACCUCCCUGCCCAAACCCCUCUGGAGUUCCCCAUUGUUCCCAGAGACAAUAGCUAGUUUCCUUUACCUGCCUCAUCAUCCCAGGCCCAGGAAUCUCUCACUCUGUUUACAAGAGGCAGCGGUGGGGUAGGAGUAUCUGGGCCUUACCCCAGGGUCCAAGGAUCUCACCGCUGGAAGAUCCCACAGCUAUGGAAACUGAGGCUGGGAGGAGUGGGAUGUGACUUAGCCAAGGUCACAGCAACCACAGAUGUGGGCCAGUGCUUGGUGGGGCCUCCACGGUUCCCCGUGGAGUACGCACUUUGGUGGUUCUCAGAGGGAGCCAUCAGGGCCUGCCGUUCCUCCCCUCGAGACUCUCUCCAGCUGUCUGUGCAGCCCAGGGGUUCUCACACACAUCCUGGGAGUGUGUUUAGAUCAGUGGAGCCCUGGAACCCAGCUGCACAGACUCUGGGGCAAGCAAACCUGGGUUUGGAUCCUGCCACAGAACCUUCAUUUAUUUGUUCCGUAAACCAAAAAAAAAGUGUGUGAGACAGAUCUCCGUCAACUUAGCGGUUUAUUUUGCCAAGGUUGACGAUAAGCCUGGGAAAAAGAGACAAAAGUUACAGAAGGCUCUGUGGCCUGUCCUUUUUCCAAAGACAGUUUCAGGAUUUCCAUUCUUAAAGGGGAAAGAGCAGCAGGAGGGAAAAGAGGAACAGUCCAUUACUGGUGAGAUUCAACAGAACUUGGCCUUAGGGUGAGGACUUUGGAGCCCACAAGGAAUUCCUCCUGAGCAAUUUGUGAGAAAGGUCACCUGGGGAAAUAUGCGGCCUUCCAUUGCUGCAGCUGUCUGUUUAGGAACCAAAAUAAGGCAGUUUUUGUGUGACUCAGUUCCCAAGCUUAACUUUUCCCUUUGUGAGUUUGGGGUCUCUUUUCCUUUCACAUUUCUUACAACAAUUUUUACUAGUAUUUAUUGCCAAGCACUGGGCCACAACAAAAUUGUUCCUACUCUCAAGUCCCUUCUCUCAAGGAACUUAUGUUUUAUUUCUUUAUUUUUAUUUAUUUAUUUAUUUUUGAGACAGAGUCUCGCUCUGUCACCCAGGCUGGAGUGCAGUGGCAUGAUCUUGGCACACUGCAACCUCUGCCUCCCGGGUUCAAGAGAUUCUUCUGCCUCAGCCUCCUGAGUAGCUGGGAUUACAGGCACGCAUCGCCAUGCCCGGCUAAUUUUUUGUAUUUUUAAUAGAGACUGGGUUUCCAUGUUGGCCCAGCUGGUGUCUCAAACUCCUGACCUCAGGUGAUCCACCCGCCUUGGUCUCCCAAAGUGCUGGGUUUACAGGAGUGAGUCACUGCGCCUGGUGGAACUUACGUUUUAGUAAGGGAGGCAGAUAACCAACAAGAUAAGGAAGUAAAAUAUAUAGCAUGUCUGACAAUGAUUUAGCAGAGAGGUAAAGAAAGUAGAGGAAAGGAUGGCAGGGCAGCUGGAGGUGGGGUGGAAGGACUGUACAUUUAAAUAGGAUGGUUGGGUAAUAUUUGAGCAAAGAUUUGAAGGAGGUCACAGAUGAAGCCACGUAGAUUUCUGGAUAAAGACCCUUUUGGUAGGUGCUUGAGCCUGAGUAGGGGCUCAGGACAUACCACUCCAAAACAGAACUGCCAGUGACUAGACUGUGCCACCCCAAAAUAUACCUCUUUGGGAUAUUGAUUAUUUCAAGCUGGUUAUUUUAAGAAACUGUAGACAUGGGAGUUGCUCUGAAAAGCUGUUCUUUUAUAAAGGAAAUCUACAUUUAACAAGGAAAUUUUCACGGGAGAGGGUAUCUAUAUCAGGAAGAGAUUUACUCCAGACAAUUUUUAUCACCUGAGAGACUUGUAUCUUACAUAGCAAGGCACACUUUAUUCACCACCCAUUUCCUCCCCUCACCCUCUUAUGUCUCCAUCACCCCUAGAGGCCCCAAACCCCUAUUGUGUAGCUCAGGAUAGUACAUAAGCCUUAAUUUUUGGGUUGUUUCUUGGGGUCUUAUAUUUUUGUGGGACUCCUGUGCAUACAUAUGAAAUUAAAAAUGUUUUUCUCCUGUAAAUCUGUCUAUGUCAAUUUAAUUCAUAGACCUGCCAAAGAACUUAGAAGGGUACCAAGAAGCAAUAUUUUUUUCUCUUCUAUAGUUGUAGAACCCCAAAACUCAGUUUGAGUACCUGAUGUGCAGGAAGCCAAACAGUGACACAUCAGUGCUUCAGAAGAGAGAAUGGUUUAUUUGAUUUGGCCAACGGUAAUAUAGGCUCUGUUACAAAGGGACCUUACUGUCUGGGACCUGCUAGCUCCAGUACUGCCACAAUGCAGGAUUCCAGGCACUGACUCACUGGCCCUGCCAUGCCCACGCCACUGCUCCCGCUGCUGCUUCGAUUGCUGCUGUCCUGCCUGCUGCUGCCUGCUGCCCGCCUGGCCCGCCAAUACCUCCUGCCCCUGCUGCGCCGAUUGGCCCGCCGCCUGGGCUCCCAGGACAUGCGAGAGGCUUUGCUGGGCUGUCUGCUGUUCAUUCUCAGCCAGCGACACUCGCCAGACGCUGGGGAGGCCUCAAGAGUGGACCGCCUGGAGAGGAGGGAGAGGUUAGGCCCCCAAAAGUGAGGCCACAAGUCCUGGCAGCAGCUGUAUCCACAAAAUGCUUUCUUUUGGAGUAGGAUAAUCCUGGCACCAGCACUGACCGAAGCCUGCCCAGUGGACAGAAGAUAUAGUGAGGGUUGUGCAUGAGAGGGAUCUGCCACAGACAUGCCUCUCCACUCCCAACAGAAAUGUCUUUCUGGAAGAAUGCCUUGCAUCUAGCACAAAACUGAUUAUUGCCCCUCUGUCCUCCAGCAGUUCCUCCCAAAGACCACUCCUAAUCACCUCUGGCCUCAGGCGGGAGGGGAACUAACACCCACCCACCCCUGCCCUCCCUGCAAAUGGGAACAUCAAGGUUCCCAGUGCUUAACUGAGGGACAAGUGACAAUUUAGCAGAGAGGCAAGAUUUGAAUCCAGACUGUCUUCCAGACUCAGGACCUACCUUAAAAUAAUAUCUGAGUUGCUUAUGGAGGCAGACCUGCCUGCAAAGCCCAGCACUCAGCAAGUGCUCAAUAAAUAUUUGAUUUGAAUUCUU